GCUGCCAGAGGCCCCCGCAUCCACCGCUGAGCUGGGAGAAAGAUGGCGGCAGCCGUGCGACAGGAUUUGGCCCAGCUCAUGAAUUCGAGCGGCUCUCAUAAAGAUCUGGCUGGCAAGUAUCGUCAGAUCCUGGAAAAAGCCAUUCAGUUAUCUGGAGCAGAACAACUAGAAGCUUUGAAAGCUUUUGUGGAAGCAAUGGUAAAUGAGAAUGUCAGUCUCGUGAUCUCGCGGCAGUUGCUGACUGAUUUUUGCACACAUCUUCCUAACUUGCCUGAUAGCACAGCCAAAGAAAUCUAUCACUUCACCUUGGAAAAGAUCCAGCCUAGAGUCAUUUCAUUUGAGGAGCAGGUUGCUUCCAUAAGACAGCAUCUUGCAUCUAUAUAUGAGAAAGAAGAAGAUUGGAGAAAUGCAGCCCAAGUGUUGGUGGGAAUUCCUUUGGAAACAGGACAAAAACAGUACAAUGUAGAUUAUAAACUGGAGACUUACUUGAAGAUUGCUAGGCUAUAUCUGGAGGAUGAUGAUCCAGUCCAGGCAGAGGCUUACAUAAAUCGAGCAUCGUUGCUUCAGAAUGAAUCAACCAAUGAACAAUUACAGAUACAUUAUAAGGUAUGCUAUGCACGUGUUCUUGAUUAUAGAAGAAAAUUCAUUGAAGCUGCACAAAGGUACAAUGAGCUCUCUUACAAGACAAUAGUCCACGAAAGUGAAAGACUAGAGGCCUUAAAACAUGCUUUGCACUGUACGAUCUUAGCAUCAGCAGGGCAGCAGCGUUCUCGGAUGCUAGCUACUCUUUUUAAGGAUGAAAGGUGCCAGCAACUUGCUGCCUAUGGGAUCCUAGAGAAAAUGUAUCUAGAUAGGAUCAUCAGAGGAAAUCAACUUCAAGAAUUUGCUGCCAUGCUGAUGCCUCACCAAAAAGCAACUACAGCUGAUGGUUCCAGCAUCUUGGACAGAGCUGUUAUUGAACACAAUUUGUUGUCUGCAAGCAAAUUAUAUAAUAAUAUUACCUUCGAAGAACUUGGAGCUCUUUUAGAGAUCCCUGCAGCUAAGGCGGAAAAGAUAGCAUCUCAAAUGAUAACCGAAGGACGUAUGAAUGGAUUUAUUGACCAGAUUGAUGGAAUAGUUCAUUUUGAAACUUCUGGCAACCACCAAUCCAUCUUCUGUCUCUGGAUUUACCUAGUCUGGAUAGUUCAUAUAAAUGGAAUCAUACAAUAUGUGACAUGUGACCUUUUGGCUGAUUCCACUCAGCAUAGUAUCUUUAGGGUUCAUCCAUGUCAUGGCAGCACGAGAAGCCCUGCCAACGUGGGAUAAGCAGAUCCAAUCACUUUGUUUCCAAGUGAAUAACCUUUUGGAGAAAAUUAGUCAAACAGCACCAGAAUGGACAGCACAAGCCAUGGAAGCCCAGAUGGCUCAGUGAAUCCUUGCAGAACUUCUGUGCACAUGACAUCUUUUUCCAUGUUGUGCAGAUCAGUUUCACUAUCUCCAAAGCAUUUGCAUCAUGACCUUAUACAUUUCAAUCCCUUUUAUGCUGGAUUCCGUUUAAAGAAGACAUUAUUAGAGCAGGAAGUACAAGCAUUUAAAAUAUGUAGUUCCCAUAUAUUUCAGGGUCUCUGUGUAUUAAGCUAACUCAGAUGUUUUGAAAGCUUUUUCUUUAAACAGAGGUGAAAUAUCUGUGGCUAAAAAGUUUGAGAUUUGUGAUAACUUUGUAGUCAUGUAAAACUUAAGUGCUUCAUGCCUCUCCAAAUGUGGUUAUUCUAAUAAAUGGAGAAAUGAGCCAAAUAAAAGUAGUACUUUGUUUUUAGUUA